CUCGCCGCGCUGAGCCGCCUCGGGACGGAGCCAUGCGGCGCUGGGCCUGGGCCGCGGUCGUGGUCCUCCUCGGGCCGCAGCUCGUGCUCCUCGGGGGCGUCGGGGCCCGGCGGGAGGCACAGAGGACGCAGCAGCCUGGCCAGCGCGCAGAUCCCCCCAACGCCACCGCCAGCGCGUCCUCCCGCGAGGGGCUGCCCGAGGCCCCCAAGCCAUCCCAGGCCUCAGGACCUGAGUUCUCCGACGCCCACAUGACAUGGCUGAACUUUGUCCGGCGGCCGGACGACGGCGCCUUAAGGAAGCGGUGCGGAAGCAGGGACAAGAAGCCGGUGAGCCCCGCCCGGGCUGCUGCAGGGUCUGAGCCCCGGACAGGGUGUGGUGGUAGCUCCCACCGGGUCCCACUGGGCCCCUCACCUGCUUCUCUCUCCCCCCAGCGGGAUCUCUUCGGUCCCCCAGGACCUCCAGGUGCAGAAGUGACCGCGGAGACUCUGCUUCACGAGUUUCAGGAGCUGCUGAAAGAGGCCACGGAGCGCCGGUUCUCAGGGCUUCUGGACCCGCUGCUGCCCCAGGGGGCGGGCCUGCGGCUGGUGGGCGAGGCCUUUCACUGCCGGCUGCAGGGUCCCCGCCGGGUGGACAAGCGGACGCUGGUGGAGCUGCAUGGUUUCCAGGCUCCUGCUGCCCAAGGUGCCUUCCUGCGAGGCUCCGGUCUGAGCCUGGCCUCGGGUCGGUUCACGGCCCCCGUGUCCGGCAUCUUCCAGUUCUCUGCCAGUCUGCACGUGGACCACAGUGAGCUGCAGGGCAAGGCCCGGCUGCGGGCCCGGGACGUGGUGUGUGUUCUCAUCUGUAUUGAGUCCCUGUGCCAGCGCCACACGUGCCUGGAGGCCGUCUCAGGCCUGGAGAGCAACAGCAGGGUCUUCACGCUACAGGUGCAGGGGCUGCUGCAGCUGCAGGCUGGACAGUACGCUUCUGUGUUUGUGGACAAUGGCUCCGGGGCCGUCCUCACCAUCCAGGCGGGCUCCAGCUUCUCCGGGCUGCUCCUGGGCACGUGAGGGCGCCCAGGGGGGCUGGCGAGGAGCUGCCGCCGGAUCCCGGGGACCCUCCUACUGAUGCCCGUGGUCACCACAAUAAAGAGCCCUCCACCCUC